AGGACAGCCGGGAGCGCACCUCGAGGGCCCGGGCAGCGGUCGAGUGGCAGCUGCGUCCAGCCCAUGCGGGAGCUGCUGCGGGUUACGGGUGGCCCCAGCUCCAGGCUCCUCCUCCAGCCGGUCCCCCACCCUCCACCCCUUCUCGACUCCGCUCUGCAAAUCGAAGGCUUUCCGGAGCAGCCUAGGAGCGGCCGCGGGCGCAGCGAAGGCGGCAGGAGGAGCGCAGCAGCCUUCGGGCAGCCGCGGCGGCGUCGCUAGAGCAGCCGGGGAGGCGCCGCGGUGCCCGGCGCGCCCUCCAAGCUAGGAGAGGGGAGAAGCCGGGGGCUGCAGCUGGGCAAGGGGGAGGAAAGUGCGUGUGCGUGCACGCCUGUGUGCAGGGCAGAGAGUGCGGGGGGCGACAGUCUCGGCUUAGGGCGGAGGAGAGGGCAGGGGAACGGCGGUGCAGCUCCCCCGCUGUCCCCGAGGAUUUCCCGCGGCAGCCCCGGGCUCCCCAGUGCCCCUCACCAUGGACUUGCGCGGAGUUGGGACGGGCCUCGGCAGCAGCAAGCGGCUGGCUGCCGGGCCCUGGGGGAGCGCGGGCGCGCGCGCGGGGAUGGCGAGGUAGGAUGGCCACCCAGCGCGACCCCCGCCGCCCCAACCCAGCGGCCCCUGGGCGGUGCCGCUGACUCGCCGGAGCGCACAGGGGUGUGGGCGGAGGCGGCCUCGCCGCGCCCGCGCCUUCGGGAGUCGCCUCGCCUCUUCCACCCACUUGCACCUGCCACCCCGCGGAUACCAUGUCGAAGGCGGCCGGAGGCGCGGCGGCGGCUGCGGCGGCGGCGGAAAGUUGUUCCCCAGCCCCGGCCGGCUCGUCCGCGGCCCCGCCCGCGCCGGUGGAGGACCUGUCCAAAGUGUCGGACGAGGAGCUGCUGCAGUGGAGCAAGGAGGAGCUGAUCCGCAGCCUGCGGCGCGCCGAGGCGGAGAAGGAUAUCAACCAGAAACUCCAGGAAGACAACCAGGAACUGAGGGACCUCUGCUGUUUCCUGGAUGAUGACCGGCAGAAAGGCAAGAGGGUGUCUCGGGAGUGGCAGAGACUGGGUCGCUACACUGCCGGGGUGAUGCACAAGGAAGUGGCCUUAUACCUGCAGAAGCUGAAAGACCUGGAGGUGAAGCAGGAGGAAGUGGUGAAGGAGAACAUGGAGCUCAAGGAGCUCUGUGUGCUACUAGAUGAGGAGAAGGGUGCAGGCUGCGCAGGCAGCCGCUGCUCCAUCGACAGCCAGGCCAGCCUGUGCCAACUCACAGCCUCCACCGCACCCUACGUGCGGGAUGUGGGUGACGGCAGCAGCACCUCCAGCACUGGCAGCACUGACAGCCCGGACCACCACAAGCACCACGCGAGCAGUGGCAGCCCGGAGCACCUGCAGAAGCCCCGGAGCGAGGGCAGCCCGGAGCACUCCAAGCACAGGAGCGCCAGCCCCGAGCAUCCACAGAAACCCAGAGCCUGUGGAACCCCAGAUCGCCCCAAAGCACUCAAAGGACCUAGCCCGGAGCACCACAAACCCUUGUGCAAGGGCAGCCCCGAACAGCAAAGGCACCCGCAUCCAGGGAGCAGCCCCGAAACGCUGCCCAAGCACGUGCUGAGUGGGAGCCCGGAACACUUCCAGAAGCACCGGUCAGGGAGCAGCCCUGAACACGCCAGGCACAGUGGAGGGAGCCCGGAGCAUCUUCAGAAACACGCUCUUGGGGGGAGCCUAGAGCAUCUCCCCAGAGCCAGGGGCACCAGCCCGGAGCACCUCAAACAACAUUAUGGAGGGAGCCCUGAUCACAAACACGGAGGAGGCAGUGGAGGAAGUGGAGGCAGCGGCGGAGGCAGCAGGGAGGGCACCCUCAGACGGCAGGCACAGGAGGACGGGUCACCCCAUCACCGGAAUGUCUACAGUGGCAUGAACGAAUCAACCUUGUCCUAUGUUAGGCAGCUGGAGGCAAGAGUAAGACAGCUGGAGGAAGAAAAUCGCAUGCUGCCCCAGGCCAGCCAGAAUAGAAGGCAACCUCCAACUAGAAACAGCUCAAAUAUGGAGAAAGGCUGGGGGUCCAGAGCCCGGCGGGUCUUGCAGUGGUGGCAAGGGUGCCGAGGAAUAGGACGAUGCCUGCCUACUCUCCCGGGUUCUUUUAGGUUGUCAUCAGGGGCUGAUGGGAGUAACAGUUCACCCAACUCUGCAGCUAGCUUCAGUGGACAUGCCACACCUUCCCAGCAGCCUGAACCUGUGGUACAUUCUCUUAAGGUCUUGGAUGUUCAGGAAACUAUAGAUCGUCAACAGGGUAAAGAGUAUGAACAUGACCUUAGUGAGACAGAAAAAGCUAUAGUCAGAGAAAUGUGCAAUGUUGUGUGGAGGAAACUUGGAGAUGCUGCAGGUUCGUGUCCUGGAAUUAGGCAACAUUUGUCAGGAAACCAGUACAAAGGACCAAUGUGAGAUGCACUCUUUUUCAAACAGGAGAUCACCACUGCCAGAAAGUGAUAGAAGACAAGAAGAAAAAGGAAAGAGUGGGUUUCCACAAACCUGGACUCAUGGAAUAACAUGGAGUGAUUGUACAUUGCACAUAUCUCCCCUCUAAAACCUGUAGUACAACUUCUCCCCUCAAGCUGAUAUUCUGUGUCUCUCACCUCAAUGUCCACAACAGUCAAUCUCAAACAAGGUAGCUUUGAACAUCUCAAACAGAGUAGCUUUGAAAAUCAACAUUUUGGUACCAGUGUUUUCAUUAGAAAUAAGUGUUUUUAACUCCCCAGAUAUAAUAUUGUAAUUGGGAAACCUGAAUAGUUUUAAGAGUCCAGUGGAGCCUCAGUGUUUUGAAUAGAGAUGACUCAUUACACAUAAUGGUAGGAGUUUUCUACCAUAUCAUAUUGAAGAUAUGAAGAGGUAUUUUCCAGCUUCCCAAGUUUGAGAGUUGGGCAUUUACCUCUUACACUUCAGUCAACAAACAAACUAGUAAUUCCUAAUGCAUAAUUAAUUUGGAUGCAAGAUAAGAUUAAGUUUCUGGAGUUUUGUUUUGACUUCUGAGGUGCUAAAAAAUACCAUGUAAAUUCUCCCUACCAGCUAGAAGGGUAGCAAGACGUUGUAGAGUGCUUAUCAGAGAGUACCAUUUACUUCAAUUGAUCAAUAUAAAUAUAUCUUUUUUUUUCAUCUUAAUGAGUUUCUCAUAAAGACACAUCUUGGGGCAUACCAACCUUCAUAUUCAUUCAGUGUAUCCAUUGGUGUUAAUAUUAACAAUUUCAACUAAAAACAACAAACAUAAUUUUUCUAAGUGUUUCGAGCUGUGAGAUGUCAAUUUCUACAAUUUAGUUUCUAGACAUGCUGUAUAUUUAAUAAACUUUAUGUAAACUUUAAAAUAUUGCACUGCAUUUAUGAAAAAAGCUUUCUUUGCCUACUGCAGCUAUCUAACAUUUUAUGAAACUGACGCAUGUCCUUCAUUAUUGAGGCUAAAAGCUCUUGUUCAGAUUGCUUGAGGUUUGAAAAAGAGGUGUGCUAGCUUUGCUUAGUUUAUUUCUUAUUUUUGGUAUACAUAUACAUAUAUAUAACAUUAGAAUGUGUGUACUGGAAAUGCUAUGAUAGGUAUUUUGUGUUAAUCCAAAUGCAAUGAUAGUUUCUUGUAUGAAUGUGCAAGAGGCCUGUGACCGAAUGCUACGUUUUUAUGGUAGUUUAAGAUUAUAAAAGUAGAAAUGCAACAAUUCCCAGUUUUUGGAUAGGUUCUAAAUUUCUGAGAUUUGAUUCAUGGCAGAUAUUCUCUGUUGUUGUUGUUUUAGAUGGGCUCAUUACAUAACGAGUUAAUUGUCACUAGUAGGAGACUGUGAAGGAAUUUUGUUAUACUUUCAAAAAUGUUACUGUGAUGAAAAAUCAUCUAUUUUCAGAAAAUAUUUAUGAAUUAAUUUACUAUAGAAUUAUCUCUCUAAUUAUCAUAAUUGGGUUACAAUUUAAGCUCCCCUUUUAAAUGUUAUAUUUUAAAAUGUUAUUACUCUAUAAAAGAAAAUUGCUUGCUAUAUUUACACCUUCUUUCCUAGGAAAGCUUUCAUCCUUAAAUUGUUGUAUUCCUACCCUCUGAAGACAUUUAAAAUAAGCUUUUGUGCCUGCAGCAGAGCCUGCAGAAGCUAAUACAAGGGACACUGGUCUUUUGACAAAAUAAACUUGUGUAAAUUUUGAUACUGUAUUAAAACUAUUUUUUUAAAGUUCUGCAUAAAAUUGAGUAUUAAGUAUAUGUGUUCAUCUUAGCAAUGGUAAUAAAUUAUUUAAUCUCACA